ACUGAGCACCAGCUGGCCAGGAUGGGUCUUCAACAAGAAAUCUCACUGGUAAGUGAUGACAGCAUGGGACCAGGGUCCCAUGAAGACCUGCUGGAGGGCCGCACCUCUGGGAAGCAGCCCUGGUGUCACCACCCUGCAGAAUCCUGUCAGACAACCACCGACAUGACAGAGCGCCUGUCGGCUGAGCAGAUCAAGGAGUACAAGGGAGUCUUUGAGAUGUUCGACGAAGAGGGCAACGGGGAGGUGAAGACGGGGGAGCUGGAGUGGCUCAUGAGCCUGCUGGGUAUCAACCCCACCAAGAGUGAGCUGGCCUCAAUGGCCAAGGAUGUGGACAGAGACAACAAAGGGUUCUUCAACUGCGAUGGUUUCCUGGCACUAAUGGGAGUUUACCAUGAGAAGGCCCAGAACCAGGAGAGCGAGCUGAGGGCGGCAUUCCGUGUCUUUGACAAAGAGGGCAAGGGCUACAUUGACUGGAACACACUCAAGUACGUGCUAAUGAACGCAGGGGAGCCCCUCAACGAGGUGGAGGCGGAGCAGAUGAUGAAGGAGGCCGACAAGGAUGGGGACAGGACCAUCGACUAUGAGGAGUUUGUGGCCAUGAUGACGGGGGAGUCCUUCAAGCUGAUCCAGUAGGUGCAGCUGCCGCAGCCGGGGGAGGCCUGCCCGGGAAGGCUGCUGCCCCUGCCCCCUGGCCCCCACUCCCCCGGCUCCGUGUAAAAUAAAUGUUCCAGCCCAA